GAGCCUGGCCCCACGUCCAGGCACCAGGACCUCCAAUCCAAUGGUGUCUUCUUCCUCCCAGUCACACUGUUCACUUUGCCCUACAGCAGCAAGGGCUAAACUAGGAGAGGCCAAAAGCCCAGGCAAGUCCUGGUUGGGCAAGCAAUUGCGAGUGAAACUGAGGACCAUCCUGACUGAGAUGGGUCUUUCAUAAGUCCCCCAAGAGCCAGGUGAGGCAUCAUCAACAUCAGCCUCUCCUGCCACCACCGCUUCCCUGAUUCAUGCACUUCAGGCUUCAGCCAGCAGCACGCAUCCUUGGGGUUAGGAGCCAGCAUCUCAGGUCAGCAGCCAUGGUUUCUCUGGAGAAAGACCCAUCAGAGGCUCAUUCAGAGCCUUAACCCUGAGCCUCUGCCACCUACCCACCGUGUUGAAGAUGUCAUUGCUUGGAAGGGACUACAACAGUGAGCUGAACUCCUUGGACAACGGACCUCAGUCACCCUCAGAGAGCAGCAGUAGCAUUACUUCAGAGAAUGUCCAUCCUGCUGGAGAAGCUGGACUAUCGAUGAUGCAAACUUUGAUCCACUUGUUGAAAUGCAACAUUGGCACAGGGCUCCUGGGGCUUCCCCUGGCCAUAAAGAAUGCCGGCUUGUUGGUCGGUCCUGUCAGCCUUCUGGCCAUCGGGGUCCUCACCGUGCACUGCAUGGUCAUCCUGUUGAACUGUGCUCAACACCUCAGCCAGAGACUGCAGAAGACUUUUGUGAACUAUGGAGAGGCCACGAUGUACGGCCUUGAAACCUGCCCGAACACCUGGCUGAGGGCCCAUGCAGUGUGGGGAAGAUGGAAUUUGGCUCUGUCACCCAGGCUGGAGUGCAGUGGCAAGAUCUCAGCUCACUGCAACCCCCACCUUCAGGGUUCAAGCAAUUCUCCUGCCCAAGCCUCCCGAGUAGCUGGGAUUUACAGGUACACUGUCAGCUUCUUAUUAGUCAUCACCCAGCUGGGCUUCUGCAGUGUUUAUUUUAUGUUUAUGGCAGACAAUUUACAACAGAUGGUGGAAAAAGCCCACGUGACCUCCAACAUCUGCCAGCCCAGGGAGAUUCUGACGCUGACCCCCAUCCUGGACAUUCGUUUCUACAUGCUGAUAAUCCUGCCCUUCCUGAUCCUGUUGGUGUUUAUCCAGAACCUCAAGGUGCUGUCCGUCUUCUCGACAUUGGCCAACAUCACCACCCUUGGGAGCAUGGCUCUGAUCUUUGAGUAUAUCAUGGAGGGGAUUCCAUAUCCCAGCAACCUACCCUUGAUGGCAAACUGGAAGACCUUCUUGCUGUUCUUUGGUACAGCCAUCUUCACAUUUGAAGGCGUCGGUAUGGUUCUGCCUCUCAAAAACCAGAUGAAGCAUCCACAGCAGUUUUCUUUUGUUCUGUACUUGGGGAUGUCCAUUGUCAUCAUCCUCUAUAUCUUACUGGGGACACUGGGCUACAUGAAGUUUGGGUCAGACACCCAGGCCAGCAUCACCCUCAACUUGCCCAAUUGCUGGUUGUACCAGUCAGUCAAGCUGAUGUACUCUAUCGGCAUCUUCUUCACCUAUGCCCUCCAGUUCCACGUCCCAGCUGAGAUCAUCAUCCCGUUUGCCAUCUCCCAAGUGUCAGAGAGCUGGGCACUGUUUGUAGACCUGUCUGUCCGCUCAGCCUUGGUCUGUCUAACCUGUGUCUCAGCCAUCCUCAUCCCCCGCCUGGACUUGGUCAUCUCCCUGGUAGGCUCCGUGAGCAGCAGCGCCCUGGCUCUCAUCAUCCCAGCCCUCCUGGAGAUCGUCAUCUUUUACUCUGAGGACAUGAGCUGUGUCACCAUUGCCAAGGACAUCAUGAUUAGCAUCGUGGGCCUUUUAGGGUGUAUAUUUGGGACAUACCAAGCCCUCUAUGAGUUGCCCCAACCCAUCAGCCAUUCCAUGGCCAACUCCACAGGUGUCCAUGCAUAAUUAUCUGUUUUUAUUCUAAUAGCUCUCCCUUCCUCCCAUCCCCAGUUUGACUUCCAUGUGGAUGUUAUAUACCUUCAUCAAAUCCCAACAUCUCUAUAUUAAUUAGUGGCGUCUUUAUCUUUCCAAGAGAAAUGCAGAUGAGAAAAGUUAGCACUGAUGUCUCUCAGGCUACACCUCUUUUGGUUUUAUAUUUUUUGGAUGGCCUUUUGUACCUCUGAACCAAAAUUAGAUUCAACUAUUCAUAUUAUCAGCCUCAUUUUAUGGAAAAGGGAUGCCACUUACCCCAAUAGCCCUUGAAACAGAGACCAAGCAUAAAUACAAAAGUAACUGUUUUCUCUACACUGCAGUAGCUGCCCUUAAAGCAUCAGAUUUAGAAAAGUGUAUGUUGGGCGAAGGGAGUUUUCUAUUUAGAUAUUCUAAGUAGAAGAGUCAUAGACAGAACAAAAACAGAACUCAGCAGUAAUUUUGUCCAACCACUGGCUCCGCCACUGAUUUCCUACUGGCCCUCAGGCAAGUUCCUCCCCAUCUCUCAGUCUAUGAAGUGAACAGUUGGACUAACUGAUUAUUAAGGACUCUGUCAACUCUGAUAUUCUGAAAGUGAAUAAAAGAAAUUAACUUAUCCACCAACCACAAAAACUGGCCAUGCUAGUGUUGGUGAGGAGGUGGAGUAACUGAAACUCCAUACCCUGCUAUGUGGAUAGAAAGUAGUACAAUCAGUUUGAUAAACAUCUUGUAGUUUCUUUAAAACUUAAACAUAUACCUACCAUAUGAUCCAACUAUUCCACUCCAGAAAAAAGAAAUAUAUAUCCAUAAAAAGACUUGUACAAAAAUAUUCAUGGUAACUUUACUUAUAAAAGCAAAGAAGUUGGAAAUACUCUAAAUGUCUAUAAACAAGAGAAUGGAUAAAUAAAUUGUGAUGUAGCCAUACAAUGGAAUAUUCCUCAGCAAGGAACAGAAACAAACUGUUGAAAUACACAAUAAAAUGUAUGAAUCUUAAAAUAAAUAUGCUGAAUGACAAAAUCCAGACCAAAAAAA